GGCUCUGCCUGGGGAAGCGGCGAGGCCUGGGGCCCUGGUCAGCUGCUCUGACGCCUUGGUGCUCCCGGGGGCAUCUCCAGGCUCACCCCAGCUUCCACGGCCCUGUCUCACGGGUCAAAGGGCCACUCAAAAGCUGCUUUGAAGACGGGGGCCCAGCCAGGAGCCGCACAGGCCUCUCCCGAGGGUCUAGGUGGCUAGAAGGGCACAAGCCACACGGCGUCGCGUCGAGAGACUGAAAUUGUCUAUGAACCGCCCUCGCCGGGUUUGAGACUAGAGAGCUGGUGUUUACACGACGUCGCAAACACCAUAAAGGGCACUAAACUGUUUCUUUAAAAGCCUUCUUUUUUUUUGAGACGGAGUCACUCUGUCGCCCAGGCUGGAGUGCAGUGGUGAGAUCUUGGCUCACUGCAACCUCCGCCUCCUGGGUUCAAGCGAUUCUCCCGCCUGAGCCUCCUGAGUAGCUGGGAUUAUAGGCACGUGCCACCAUGCUCAGCUGGAGUUUCACUCUUGUCGCCCAGGCUGGAGUACAGUGGUGCUAUCUCGGCUCACUGCAACCUCCACCUCACGGGUUCAAGUGAUUCUACUGUGACGGCCUUCCAAGCUCGGGGCCAGGCUUGUAUGUCCUGCCGUCCACCGUGGGCUUCAUCAACCACGACUGCACCAGGGUGGCCAGUCCCGCCUACUCGCUCGUCCGGAGGCCCAGUGAGGCACCACCUCAGGACACCAGCCCGGGCCCCAUCUACUUCUUGGACCCCAAAGUCACACGCUUUGGCCGCAGCUGCACCCCUGCCUACUCCAUGCAGGGCCGGGCCAAGUCUCGGGGUCCGGAGGUGACGCCAGGCCCUGGGGCCUACAGCCCAGAGAAGGUGCCCCCUGUGCGCCAUCGGACACCGCCGGCUUUCACCCUGGGCUGCCGCCUCCCCCUGAAGCCCCUGGACACCUCAGCCCCUGCCCCUAAUGCCUACACCAUGCCCCCUCUGUGGGGCUCACAGAUCUUCACCAAGCCCAGCAGCCCCAGCUACACGGUGGUGGGCCGCACCCCCCCCGCCCGCCCCCCGCAGGAUCCUGCUGAGAUACCAGGCCCGGGCCAGUACGACAGCCCGGACGCAAACACCUACCGCCAGCGCCUGCCUGCCUUCACCAUGCUGGGGCGGCCCCGGGCCCCGCGACCCCUGGAGGAGACCCCCGGCCCUGGCGCCCACUGCCCAGAGCAGGUCACCGUGAACAAAGCCAGGGCUCCAGCGUUCUCUAUGGGCAUCCGCCACUCGAAACGGGCCAGCACCAUGGCCGCCACCACGCCCUCCCGGCCUGCGGGGCACAGGCUGCCCGGCCGCUGCUGCUAGGCCAGGCCUGUUUCCCACACAGUGAACGGGGGGCUGGCGGGCCUCUCCUGGGGCCUGGCUUUGGCUGGAGGGGCUAGAAGGCGAGAGGGGCUGGGAAAGGAGUCUUCCCUCCCCUUUCCUGAACUGUCCAGGUCCUUCUAGGACACCUGAUCCUUCCAGUCCCUGGGGGCUGUGACCCAUGGCCCUGUGCAGGGUGCAGGGUGAGUCUCCUUCCAGUGCCCCAGUUUCUUCCAGGUCACGCCAGGCCAGGCCAGGCCAGGUGGGGAAAGGGACACCUUCCGGCCCUCCCCAGUAGCUGGCUGGAGAUGGAGCUUCCUGUGUCCCAGAACUCGGCGUCCAGCUCCACUAGGGCCUGGAUCCCCAUCACAGCUUGGGUUAGCCCCGGUCCCAGCCCAAACUCAGGCUGGAGGCAGCCCCGAGGCCUGUGCCUUUCCCACUCCACCUUCUACAGUUGCUUAGCCAAUAAACCUUUCCUGGGCUGGA